GGAGGUGCGCUCGCCGGUGCUGUGUUUGGCGGGUGGUGGCGGCGGCGGCGGCGACGGCGACGCGCACAGAGGCGGACUGUGGCUUCCUUGGUGCUCGCGGCGGGCUGCGGGCCGGGCCGCCCGCCCUCCCCGCCGCCGCCGCCCCCGAGCCUGCGGGCGGCGCCGAGGCCGAGGAGCGCUCGCUGCAGCACAUGCUGCGUGCCAUAGCGGAGGAGCGCGGCCGUCUUAGCCUGCGCCGCGAGGUCUGCGGCCUCGGGUGCUUCAAGGAUGACCGCAUCGUCUUCUGGACUUGGAUGUUCUCCACCUACUUCAUGGAGAAAUGGGCUCCCCGGCAGGACGACAUGCUUUUCUAUGUGCGCCGGAAGCUGGCGUACUCCGGCAGCGAAAGCGGUGCAGACGGGAGGAAGGCAGCUGAGCCUGAGGUGGAGGUGGAGGUGUACCGGCGGGACUCCAAGAAGCUGCCAGGCCUGGGAGACCCUGACAUCGACUGGGAGGAGAGCGUCUGCCUGAAUCUCAUCCUGCAGAAGCUGGACUACAUGGUGACCUGUGCGGUGUGCACACGUGCUGACGGCGGGGACAUUCACAUCCAUAAGAAGAAAUCUCAGCAAGUGUUCGCGUCCCCCAGUAAACACCCCAUGGACAGCAAGGGGGAGGAGUCCAAGAUCAGCUACCCCAACAUCUUCUUCAUGAUUGACAGCUUCGAGGAGGUGUUCAGCGACAUGACCGUAGGGGAAGGAGAGAUGGUCUGUGUGGAGCUGGUGGCUAGUGACAAAACCAACACGUUCCAGGGGGUCAUCUUUCAGGGCUCCAUCCGCUACGAGGCGCUCAAGAAGGUGUAUGACAACCGGGUGAGCGUGGCCGCCCGCAUGGCACAGAAGAUGUCGUUUGGCUUCUACAAGUACAGCAACAUGGAGUUUGUGCGCAUGAAGGGCCCCCAGGGCAAGGGCCACGCCGAGAUGGCGGUCAGCCGAGUGUCUACAGGUGACACAUCCCCCUGUGGGACUGAAGAGGACUCCAGCCCAGCUUCGCCCAUGCACGAGCGGGUGACCUCCUUCAGCACACCCCCCACCCCAGAACGGAACAACCGGCCUGCCUUCUUCUCCCCAUCCCUCAAGAGGAAGGUGCCCCGGAACCGGAUCGCUGAGAUGAAGAAGUCGCACUCGGCCAACGACAGCGAGGAGUUCUUCCGGGAGGACGACGGUGGAGCCGAUCUGCACAAUGCAACCAACCUGCGGUCUCGGUCCCUGUCGGGCACAGGACGGUCCCUGGUCGGGUCCUGGCUGAAGCUGAACAGAGCAGAUGGAAACUUCCUUCUCUAUGCACACUUAACCUACGUCACGUUGCCGCUGCAUCGGAUUUUAACAGACAUCCUGGAAGUUCGGCAGAAGCCCAUCCUGAUGACCUAGCCGCGUGCGGAGCCUGCGCAGAGCCCCGGCCGGGCCCAGCCCUCGGAGUGCUGCCAAGUGCCUACCUGUCCACCGCCACCGGGGUCUGCGAUGGCACGCCAGUGCUGGAGCCGCAGCCAGGCGAGGCCACUCGACUCCCGGGGCCGGGGCCGACUCCACGAACACCAGCCCAAACUGAAGUGCCUCUUCCCUCCCCUGCUGGCGCUGCUCCGCCCUGUGCCCCCCGCCCAUCGCCCCCCACCCAUCUCUGGAGAGCCCUCUGCACCCAAAGAGGACUAGAGAUGCCGAGCGGCCAUGAGAGAGAGCGGAAGGAGCAGCUGAUGCCCAGAGCGGGGCCAGAGCGGCGGGUCUAUGUUCACGUCCCCCCAGCAGCAGGCGGAACCACCCAGCCAGGGCACUCAGUGCAUUGGACUGUCCACAUGUUCUUGAGGAAAGCCGGUGGAAGAUUCUGGAAUGCCGUGCGGAUGAACUUCAGCACCCGAGUCAGUCCCAGCUCAUCCUCCCCAGUUUACCACUUUGUUCUAAUAGGAGAUGGGAACACGAGAAGUUUGAUGGCUUUGCCCUGGGCUGGGAAUACCUCACCCACGCCCAGUUCCAGAAAGGCCUCCAGCUGAGCAGACGGCCCCGAUCCCGCCAGAACGGCCUUUUGCUUCCAGCCAAAGAACACCGCCAACACGCACACCUCCAACCUGGGACAUCCCACGCUGGGCCUCGCACGGAGGAACCUGCAGAAUUUGGAUUCUGAGGGUAGUCGGGAGGCCUCGGUAGCCAGGCAGAACAGGAUAUCUGCCAAAGGGUGUCUGAUGUGGGGUGGGGCUGGCAUCCUCCCAGGAAGGUUCUAGGUGGGACCCCGUCUUCUGGGGGCGGGGGUGUCUUUUCAUCUUCCCUGGUUUCCUAGAACUCACUUCCUUUGACGGCGUGUGUUGGUCCCAUCUCUCAGACCAGCUCACUGAGGCAGAGGAGUUGCUCAGAGGCUCACAUGGGCACCCCCAUUGGUUCGUGUGAGCAGCUGCCCAGCCCCAGGCCUGCCCUCGGCCUGGUCCAGCAUGAAGGCGUUUCCAUCUGCAAGGAUGCACGGUACCCUCCCCGAGAGCAGGCCUGUCCCCUACCCAACUGGGAAUAAACUGGAAGCUGGGUCUCUUUGUUGCUAUGUUUUUUUGUUUGAAGUUCCCAGGAAUAUUUGAGGGGUUCCGGUGAUGUGUUUAGGGAUCUUCUCUGUGGGGGAAAAGGAAGAGGAGGGUCUUGUUCUCCCAUCUGUUUAUUCUUUGGGCUCUGGGAACAGGGGACUACUUUGGGGCUUUCUCCAGACUUUUGUAUGUUGUUAUUAAAAGCGAGCUAUUGCAUUUCAUUCUGCCUCAGUUUGCCCACCUGUGAAAUGGGGCUGAUACCACCUACCUCACUGAAGUCCCAGGGUUCAAGUGUGUGGCUGGGUCAGGGCGUGGUCACCCGUCAUUCUGCAUAGGUCGGGUUGGAUGUUAGACUCCUGGGAUGCCCUCCUCCCCCUCGCCCUUUGUAAUAACCUAAUCUGAGACCGUGCUUGGUGGGGGGAUGUGAACUUUCUCUCUCCCCCAGCAGUGUCUGCUCAGGCCUGACAGCUCAGCUCUGCACGAUUUCAUGUUCCUAAACCCAUGUCUUAGGGCAGCACAGAGCCAGGUCAUGUCAUGCCCCAAAGUGUGGGGACAGAGCCUCAGGGAGCCCCGAGCAUGGUCCAGCCCCAUUUGAGUGCUCUCCGGGGAUGCCAAAUGCUGCUUCCAAGUUUGAGUCCAUGUGGCUAAAAUACACCCAUUUCUUCAGGAACUCUUCCCCUGGUUGUUCUGGGGAUCUUGGGAGAAACACAGCCCUGACAGCUCGUCCGUGGGAAGAUGAGGCAGUCCAGGUUGUGAGGAGCACAGCGGCCCGCCCUCUGUUCUCAGAGGUGAGGGGCGGGAGAAGGUUGUCUCCUCUGGGGCCAGCAUUUGGCCAAGCUCGGAGGCUUGGCCAGCACUGCUGGAUGGCUCAGAGCAAGCUGGGCUCCCCGUCUGUAAGAUGGCAAAAAUGCUGCCCCCCUCACAGGGUGACCAUGAGGACCAGUCACAGUGAUGUGUGAAAGGGCUCGCUGGUCACAGAAACGUGUACAAAUCAUGCUAUUUUAGAGAUCAGCCCUCAAUUUGUAAGGCAUGUGAACAGGGCACGCGGUGGGCUGGUGGUUUCAUAGCCGACACACAGCGCCUACCAUGUGCAGCUGCCUGUCCGACCCCAUCUUACAGACGAGAAAACCAGCACACAGGCACCAAGGAACUGUCCGGAACUAACAGCAGGGGCCGGCGAUGGGAGUCAAACCCAGGCACGCGGCCUGGCCUGCAUGCUGAGCCACAUGGUGCUGUCCGGACAGAUGGACAGACACUCGGUGGAGUCUGCCUUUCUCAGGCCCUAAAUCCCUCUCCAAAGGGUACUUGCGAUGCCGGAUUUAAAACUUGCUCAGAGCCACUUAGCCACUUGAGAACCAGACAGUAAGGUGUUACUCCCAGGUUUGUUUUUCCAAAGUAACAGAUGACAUGUGGAAUAAAGUAAUAGAGUAACAAGUGGCAGGGCCAGAACCAGGGUCCCCAAAGUCCUGGUGUUGGCACAUUUGUACUUCUUGUAAGACCAUCUUUAAUUUUUCUGGGAACACACCUGCCUUUUGUGUAAUGCGGGGAAGACUAAUGCAUGGUGACACCUAGUUUUCCUCAACAGGACACUUGAUCCCAAAACCCCUUUAAGACCUUAGGUUUCCUCAGCGGAAAACUGUACUUUAAUCCCAAACCCCCUUUAAGACAUAUUGGGGCUGGGCGCAGUGGCUCACGCCUGUAAUCCCAGCACUUUGGGAGGCUGAGAUGGGUGGAUCACCUGAGAUCAGGAGUUCAAGACCAGCCUGACUAACAUGCUGAAACCCCAUGUCUACUAAAGAUAGAAAAAUUAGCUGGACAUGGUGGCAGGCACCUGUAAUCCCAGCUACUCGGAAGGCUGAGGAAGGAGAAUCACUUGAACCUAGUAGGCAGAGGUUGCAGUGAGCCGAGAUCACGCCAUUGCAUUCUAGCCUGGGCAACGAGAGCGAAACUCUGUCUCAAAAAAAAAAAAAAAAAAAAAAAAAAAAAAAAAAAAAAAGAUACAUUGGUCUUUAAACCCAAACCCCCUUUAAGGCAUGUUGGUCUCAAGGGGAUUUGGGAUUGAAGCACAGCUUUCUGUUGAGGAAACCUAGGUGUCACUUUUUAGAACAUUAAAAAGAAAGUUGUAGGGUGGGCUUUUCCAUUUAAAGGAAUGUGAUGAUCCUAGGUUCUGAUGAGUGAUAGGUGGUCUCCGUUUAUACCCUUUCUUCUUUUGGCACCUGUAAGUUCCGGUAGUGGCCAUCUUACAUUCUCAUGUCCUGCUGGAAGUGCCUAGUUGCCUGCAAAGCCAGCUAAGGCUUAUUAUUUCAAAAGAAGAUUAUUUAAAACAUGAGUGACAGGUAGUCAGAAGAGAACAAAAGGACGCAAGAUACUCUAUAGCCAAGUCAGCUUGGAGGCAGGAUGGGUUGCUGAGUGAAGUCGCCGCUCACUUUUGGAUUCUUAUGGACUGUGAGUUAGUCUUCCCUCUACACGGAGUCACAGGAAGGGUAUAAAUGCAUGUUCCUGAGGUGCCCUCCCCCAAAGAAUGUACCUGCACUCAAACCAGGAUCUGUUUUUGCUGUUUUAAUCAUAAAUAGACUAGUUAGUAGAAGACUUUUGAAGAACAAAGUAAAACUUUUUUUUUUCAUUAAAAGAUGUCCCAGAGGAAAGGCCCUGUGCAGCCAGUAUAUUCUAAUGACUGCCUGGACCAUGUCCUAAUAUGGUGGUUUUAAGUUGUUGGCCAAAAUCCUUUAAAGACAUACGAAACAUCUGCCAACUUUUUAGCGAACUUAACAGGUUUCACUGACGUUUUCCUCAAUUUUUGAAUUUAGGUGGGAUUUGCUUUCAUGUCCUGUUUCAAAAACCAAGUGUCUCUUGACAGCCCACUGGUUCUUCCUGUCCUCUUGCUCUAGUCUGUAUCAGAAAGCAGAAUGACUGUACUUUUGUUUUACAAACAACCACCUGAUAGGACGGACACUCCACGAGAUAAGGAAAGGCACGUGCCCUUGAGCUUGAAUGGAAGCAGCCUCUGGAGGGGGCAGCCACUGCCCUUCGAGGGAGAGCAGCUCUUCAGCAGUGGCCAGAGUGCCACGUGACUCUGCAGAUGACCCCUGGGAGCCGGGUGAUGGGCACCUGCUGGGGCUUUUGUUUUUUCUUUUUCACUGGCUGGCUUGAUCCUCAGUGGCAAAAGGACCCCUGAGCCCCUUCUCCGAGCCCUGGAGCACUCCUCGGGACACCGAGUGGCCUCAGGGCUGGGUUCAGAGCUCCUCCCGCAGGGGGAGCCUCAGAAGUGGAGGCAGCUGCUGAUGGGUGAGUUUACAACUUCUUAUCCUGCCUAAGGCGAGUAGGCGUUUUUAUUCCGUUUCCAGUCCUUGAGCUCAGCAGAUCAAAAUAACAGUGACCCUGCAACCCCACAGAGCCCGCGACACGCUCGCUUUCUUCCCCGCCCUGCCCCUUUAGUCCCCGCUCUGGAAGGCCAGGCAGUUUAGGUGUAAAUAGGUAUCUUUUAUGGUUUCCAAAUGAAUUAUUUGUGUGAGAGUAAUUAAAUCUGUAAGAAAACCUGUUGAGAUUCUUCACUAUGAAUUAUGACUUCUACAACAUGUAUUUUAGCAAAAACACGAUGCUGGCCUCCACUGGAUAGCUCAGUAUGCUGAUUGCCAGUGAUAGUUCUGUACGCGUUACCAACAGCGUCUUUAUUAACCCUCUUCCACAUCCAGUGGAAAUCAUUGCUAGGCGGUAUUUGUUGGUUGGCUGUUAGCUUUGCUUUAUGAUUUCAUGUUUCUUUUAAAGGUUGUUUUGCAUGUUGAAUAUUAAAUUUUUUUUUUCUGUG